GAAGGCAGAGGGCGUCCAGGUCCGCUCGGUAACCGUUUCCCGCGCGCCCGGCCCCGACUCCGGGGUAAAGAGCCCCGGAGCGGAGCAGCGCUGGCCGCGUGCCGCCUCCGGAGCCGGCAGCGUGAGUGGCCCCGCGUCCCCGCUUCUCCCGGUCCCCGGCGGGGCCGCGUCACCCGGCCCCGCCCCGCGCCGCCCGCCCCGCCCCGGACGCGGGGGUAAGGGGGGUGGCCGCCCGCCUGCCCUCGGUCCCGUGCGGUCCCCGAAACUCCGAGCACCCGCCCGGUCCCGGCGCGGAGCCCCUCGGCGUCGCGUGGAGCUGCGAGUCGCCCGCUUCCGGAAGCGCACACGGGCCAGUUGCGGCGGCCCAUCUGCCGGGGCGGCGGGGGCUCGGCGGGAGGGUUGAGGCUGAAUCACGCGCAGCCUGCGGGCGGCGGAAACGUCCCUAGAGCCUCGCCGCCCUGGGACCCGGGCUGCUUCCUGGGAGAGGAUUACAUUUUCUCCCUGCUCCACUUGACUUUCUUCCGGAAGGAGCAGGUCUCGCAGGAUCGGGGCCAAGACUGGAAGAGUUCAGGUUUGGGAGUCGUGUGUAUAACAGCCCCGCGCCUCCACGCCCAGGCCUGUGUGGCUUUGGACAAGUUAUAUAACCACCGCCGCCACCCCAGUUUCUUCUCCUGUAAAAUGGAGCUUUAGUGCCGCCCAGCAGGGUUGUUGGGAUAAUUCAGUGACUCUGUGGACUGCCCAGCACCUGUGAAUUGCUUUCCUGGAUGUUGGGUGAAGGCCUGUGAGCUUGUAUGUACCCUUUGGCUUCAGAAUACCAAGCCUUUAGUGUUUCAGAGGGAUGAGAGAAAGAAAUCCCAUUUUUUGAUGCAGAGGAUUUUGUUCCCCAUGGCUGGGGGUUAUGGAGUGAUGGGUGACGAUGGUUCUAUUGAUUAUACUGUUCACGAAGCCUGGAAUGAAGCCACCAAUGUUUACUUGAUAGUUAUCCUUGUUAGCUUCGGUCUCUUCAUGUAUGCCAAAAGGAACAAAAGGAGAAUUAUGAGGAUAUUCAGUGUGCCACCUACAGAGGAAACUUUGUCAGAGCCCAACUUUUAUGACACGAUAAGCAAGAUUCGUUUAAGACAACAACUGGAAAUGUAUUCCAUUUCAAGAAAGUACGACUAUCAGCAGCCACAAAACCAAGCUGACAGUGUGCAACUCUCAUUGGAAUGAAACCUCAGAAAAAGAGCAACAGAAGUAAUUGUUUCAAGCUCCUGAUUCUUUCUACUAAAUCAUGAACAGCUUUAAAAACAUUUCUGUCUGCAUAAAAUUAUUUUACUUGUAACUUUUCCCCAAUUGUUCUGUGCAUUGUUUUGCCUUUUUAAAUUACAUCUCCAAGUGGCUCAAAAGGCCUUGACACAGGGAACCUGCACAUAUCCAGGAUAUGUGUAACCAGCGAUGGUGACUUGACCUUGCCAAGACCUGUGAUUCCUUCAGGAUACAAUCAGUGAGAAAUAAAAACACAUCUUGGGAAGUGGGAAUCCUGGAGUUUAUGCCAUUUGCAAUAUUAAAAAAUAAAAAUGCAAGUUAUUAUUUCAAUAAUAACUUCCUGUUUCAUUGUAUUCUGUGAGUGAUAAGUGUCAGAUCAAUAACAGAUUAAUUUGUUGUUAACAGCUCUUUUUUUUUUUUUUUUUUUGAGACAGAGUCUGUUGCCCAGACUGGAGUGCAGUGGCACAAUCUCUGCUCACUGCAACUUCCACCUCCCGGGUUUAAACGAUUCUCCUGCCACAGCCUCCUGAAUAUUCUGUUAACAGCUCUUUAAUUAAUGAUCUUUGCUUCUUCAGAACUUGUAUGGUAGACCGUCUUUUCUACAGCAUGAUGCAUACUCCUGUGCUAAUUUUAGAAGCUUUCUGUAACUAGAUUUUUCCUCAUUAUGCUCCCAGGAGCGAGUUUGUUUUUAUCCCCGUUUCAUUUCUACCAGGUAGCUCUACUUUAGGCCAUACUGGGGACCUGCUGUUGAAUAAAUGGAUGCCUGUGUAUUGGUGUUGGCAACUCUGCGGUAGUAGUGCUACCACUGGCGAGGCAGUAUUACUGCCACUGGUGAAUGUUGCUGUCUGGUUACUGCUGCAUUUUUGGCAUGCUAAGCUUUCCUAAAGAGCCUCAUAUCUUUUCCCAUGCUGUACUGUACAAUGAAAUGUUUUUACCUAAUUUUUCAUGUUUAUUUAAAUAAAAGCUGACUGGGUAAUAGUGGGGAAGUUUAAUUGUCCACAUAAGUCAAAAGAAUCCGUUUUUGAACUAGAGCUAUUUUCAAUUAUAAGAGUGAGCUGGCUGGGCACGGUGGCUCACGCCUGAAAUCCCAGCACUUUGGGAGGCCAAGGUGGGAGGAUCACGAGGUCAGGAGUUUGAGACCAGCCUGGCCAACGUGGUUAAACCCAAUCUCUACGAAGAAUACAAAAAUUCGCUGGGUGUGGUGGCAUGCGCCUGUAAUCCCAGCUACUCAGGAGGCUGAGGCAGGAGAAUUGCUCGAAUCUGAGAGGUGGAGGUUGCAAUGAGCCAAGAUCACACCACUGCAUUCCAGCCUAGGCGACAGAGCAAGACUUCGUCUCAGAAAAAAAAAAAAAAGUUAAUAAUGGCUUCAAGUAUUUCAUUUUCCCCUUAUUGUGAAAUAAACUAUAUACAUUUUAAAUGGAAAUUAAGGUUUAGACCAAAUAAAAUCAUUCAGGGAAAUUGCAUUUACUUUUAAAAAUGUGUUGUUCAAAAAUGUAUAUAUAGUACAAAGUGAAUUGACCAAACAGAAUAAUUCUUAACUCACAAAGGAGUUUGAGCGCACUUCCUACAUGUUGAAUUUAAAUCUGACUAAAGGAUUGUAAACAGUUGUAAUUAUGGGUUGUAGUAACAGAGCAACAAGGGGACAAUCUUCUAAACUUGCCUUUGCCUAGGAGAGCUACUGUAUAUUUCCACAAGUGAAUUUAAUCAGCAGUAGGAGUGGUUUACUCGUCACUGACAUGUGGCACAAUCUGGACAAAUUACACAAACUGGCUAUCUCAGAUGUGUAAAAUUAAUGUACAUAAAUAAACGUAAGUCACACAAUGAAUUUCCUUUGUGUCCACUAGAUAGAGAUGGUCCUAACUACAAACUAGUAGAUUAUUUGAUGAGCAUCAAGCCCUGGCAAGUGACAGGAGAUGAAUUCCUCUCCGUUUUUUCCUUAAAGCAAACUGAUGGGAAUUGCACACACCCCACUGGCAGGAACAACAGCAAGCCGGCUUUGAAGUCUCUUCCCUGCUUCAACAGCUGAAUUGGGGAGAGCGCAAGCCCUGCAGCCACACUUCAAAGCGGCGCUGACUGGCUGUCCUGCUUCUACCCAACAUCCACCUGAGACUCAACAGAACUGUUUUCUUUGGAAGAAAAAUGGAACUACUAAUAAGCUAGUAAUUAACCCUUGUAUUCUUUUUCUGGUUUCAUCUUCCUGUUUUAAUGUGUAAGAUAUUCAGCAGUAAGCACUGGUCAGCCUGCCCUGGUGCACAGCUUGAGUGUGUUAAAUAACUGGCUGUUUAGCUGAUGCCAGCCAGCUGCGUGAAGGGGAGAAGGCCGCCUCCAAGGACACAGAUGUUUGCUGUUGACCUCACGCUGUGUCUGGUUGAGUUAUUCAUGAUUCAUCAGAAAAUGACAUGCAAGGUUUAUGGUAAAACUGCUGUACAAUCAGAAGUAUUUUAAGUAUGCAUUAGAAGUAAGAUAAAAUAGUAAUAAAAAUAGUUUCAGAUGUUAAGAUGAUACAAGAAUAAAUUUAACCUAGAAAAUAAAGGGAGAAGGAAUAAAAGAA